AUUCUUCCCCUCUCUACAACCCUCUCUCCUCAGCGCUUCUUCUUUCUUGGUUUGGUGCUUCUGAGAUGUGGGCUUGCACACGCUGUUGCUAUAGUACGUGUUGAUCCUGACUGCUGUCAUGGCGUGCCCUCUGGAGAAGGCCCUGGAUGUGAUGGUGUCCACCUUCCACAAGUACUCGGGCAAAGAGGGUGACAAGUUCAAGCUCAACAAGUCAGAACUAAAGGAGCUGCUGACCCGGGAGCUGCCCAGCUUCUUGGGGAAAAGGACAGAUGAAGCUGCUUUCCAGAAGCUGAUGAGCAACUUGGACAGCAACAGGGACAACGAGGUGGACUUCCAAGAGUACUGUGUCUUCCUGUCCUGCAUCGCCAUGAUGUGUAACGAAUUCUUUGAAGGCUUCCCAGAUAAGCAGCCCAGGAAGAAAUGAAAACUCCUCUGAUGUGGUUGGGGGGUCUGCCAGCUGGGGCCCUCCCUGUCGCCAGUGGGCACUUUUUUUUUUCCACCCUGGCUCCUUCAGACACGUGCUUGAUGCUGAGCAAGUUCAAUAAAGAUUCUUGGAAGUUUU